AUGUGCAGCGGCCACAGGCCCCUGAGCAGCCCCCGACCCAUGGCAGACCCCGCUGCUCGUCAUAGACCGAGCCCCCAGCGCAGCGGACGGCGCCUUCCCGGACCCCUGGCUGCGCCUCCGCGCCGCGCCCUCUCCGGACCCCGCGCCGGGCCGGCAGCGCAGAUGUGCGGGCCAGAUGUGGCGCCCGCUCGCCAGCCAGGAGGGGGCCUGGAGGCCGGCGAGGCGCGGGGAGGCCCCCGGCGGCCGAGGGAAGCUGCACAGGAGUCCGGCUCCUGUCCCGAGCGGGUGCACGCGCGGGGGUGUCGUCGCUCCGUGCGCGCGAGUGACUCACUCAACUUCAACUCAGCGCUGCGGGGGAAACAGGAAACUCCUCGCCAACAGCUGGGCAGGACCUCUCUCCGCCCGAGAGCCUUCUCCCUCUCCUCGACGUCCAGCCCCUAGCUCUCUCGUAGCUGCCAAUCAUGUUUCCUAGACCAGCCCCUCCGAGAGCUUUGGCCGACUUUCAGCUGCCCCUCACCGCCCUCCCACACCACUCAGGAGUUCCUCGCUCCAAGUAUUUACUCAAGAAUGACUAAGUGCACACAGUUCACAAAGUAACAACAGAAAACGUCCACGUUUUCCCUAGUAGAUCAGAACAUCUGCCGCCUCCCCUCAGCUUUCUUCAGAUUGCUCCUAGGUGCUUUAGAGAUGCGUUUUCAAAUUGCAAGUUGAGAUCCAGGAGUGAAUACUCCAAUCUAUUGAGUCGCGAGCACAUUUCUUUCCCAAAUAAAAUAGUAACGAUAUGUCCUGAUUGGAUAAUAAACUAUGUGAUCAACCUACUUCCCACUCUCAAAGAUAUGAUUCUGUACAGCCCUCUGGUCAGUAGAUCUUCUAGCAAUUCAUUUAAUGAAUUCCUUUACCUGAGAGGAAGAUUGCAGAGGCAAGGGUUUGUGCCAGGGUCUCCAGGGAAUAAAGGUAAAUAGCCCUCCCCCAAACCCAACUCCCAAAUCUUUCCUGUCAUUCUAAGUGUUCAUUUGCUUCAUCCUGGAAUUUUAACUCAUGCUCCACCUAGCACCCAAGCUGCCUCUGGAUGUUUUGCCACUUCCCAGUACUCAUGUUGAAGAUGCAGAAAGUGCAGUGAAAUCAGGAGGGCUAGGCAUCUUCUUUCCCACCAAUUAAUUGCCUUGCCAAAGCUGGAGUGACUUUGUCAAUGGAGGAAGAUUGAGUUCCAAAUCUUCUCCCUAUUCCCUCUUCUGCCACCAGCCCAUGCCACUGCCAUGGCUUGUGUAGGAGUCUCCCACGAGUCACCCUCAGCCACGGCCGUUCUGGGCUCUUUCACUCAGUUUCUCAAACGAGAGCUGAAUUCAGCUUUUCAAAAUACAAAACUAGUUAUACCAACCCUCUGAUUAAAAUCAUUUAAUGGCUUCCCACUGCUCUUGAGAUAAAGAGAAGAUAAAAACCAGAUCCUUGAACGUGUCUUCAAGCCUCCAACUCUCCCGUAAACUUUCAUUUGGCUUCUCCUUGCUUACUGAAAGCCUUCUCCAAAUUUCGUGAAUAUGCCUCUGUAAUCCUCCUACCCUUUAUGCUUAGAGCCUUCCCCAGUGUGGACUUCCUUCCUCUGACCUUUUUUUCUUCACCCAGCCAACUCCUGGUCUUCGUGGAUUGAAUCAUAACUUCUUUGAUGGGCAAGCUUUCCCUCACCUCCAUGAGUAGAUCUUGUAUUACACGUUCUCUUGGCACCAUAUGCUUUUCUUUUAACAGCUGUAACUUUAUAAUUAUUUGUGUCAUUCUUUAAUUUAUAUUUCUAUCCUCCACUCAACUCCAAAUUUCUUGAGGGCAGGUAUUAUGUAUCUUUCCCUCCACUUACUAUUGUGUCCCUAAGCAUCAAACACAUAAUCGAUGUUUAAUAAAUAUUUGUUGGAUGAAUGAAUGAAUCAGGCAAUAAAGAUUUAGAAGAAAA